AUAUCCGGGUUCCCGCCGCCUCCACCGCCACCGCCUCAGCCGCCUCGCACAUUUAGUCUUGCCGGGAGUGGUGUGAUUCCCGACCAAGAUGGCGGCCGUGGGGCGAGUCGGCUCCUUCGGUUCUUCUCCGCCGGGAUUAUCCUCGACUUACACUGGCGGCCCCUUGGGCAACGAGAUAGCGUCGGGCAACGGUGGCGCCGCGGCAGGCGACGACGAGGACGGGCAGAACCUUUGGUCCUGCAUCCUCAGCGAGGUCUCCACCCGCUCGCGCUCCAAGCUCCCUGCGGGGAAGAACGUGCUACUGCUGGGUGAAGAUGGAGCUGGAAAAACAAGCUUAAUAAGAAAAAUUCAGGGAAUAGAGGAGUAUAAGAAAGGAAGAGGAUUGGAAUAUUUGUACUUAAAUGUGCAUGAUGAAGACAGGGAUGAUCAAACAAGAUGUAAUGUUUGGAUCUUAGAUGGAGACCUAUAUCACAAAGGCCUCCUUAAAUUUUCACUGGAUGCCGUAUCUCUGAAGGAUACUCUAGUUAUGCUGGUUGUUGACAUGUCAAAGCCUUGGACUGCUUUGGAUUCUUUACAGAAAUGGGCAAGUGUUGUUAGAGAACAUGUUGACAAACUGAAAAUCCCUCCUGAAGAAAUGAAACAAAUGGAACAAAAGUUGAUUAGAGACUUCCAAGAAUAUGUAGAGCCAGGAGAAGACUUCCCGGCUUCUCCCCAGAGAAGAAAUACUGCGUCACAAGAAGACAAAGAUGACAGUGUAGUUUUACCUCUGGGUGCGGAUACACUUACACAUAACUUGGGCAUUCCAGUACUAGUAGUUUGCACAAAGUGUGAUGCCAUUAGUGUAUUGGAGAAAGAACAUGACUACAGAGAUGAACAUUUUGAUUUUAUUCAGUCACAUAUCCGGAAGUUUUGUUUACAGUAUGGUGCAGCACUUAUUUACACUUCAGUAAAAGAAAACAAAAAUAUAGACUUAGUAUAUAAAUACAUCGUUCAGAAACUAUAUGGAUUUCCCUAUAAGAUUCCUGCUGUUGUUGUGGAAAAGGAUGCAGUAUUUAUUCCAGCAGGGUGGGAUAAUGAUAAGAAAAUAGGAAUAUUACAUGAAAAUUUUCAAACAUUAAAAGCAGAAGAUAAUUUUGAAGACAUCAUAACUAAACCACCUGUUCGAAAGUUUGUACAUGAGAAGGAAAUUAUGGCAGAAGAUGAUCAGGUGUUUCUUAUGAAGCUACAGUCCCUUUUAGCAAAGCAACCACCAACUGCAGCUGGAAGGCCUGUGGAUGCCUCACCAAGAGUCCCAGGAGGCUCCCCACGAACACCAAAUAGAUCUGUAUCAUCUAAUGUUGCCAGCGUGUCACCCAUUCCUGCUGGGUCAAAAAAAAUUGAUCCAAACAUGAAAGCUGGAGCUACAAGUGAAGGCGUUCUGGCAAAUUUCUUCAACAGUUUGUUGAGUAAAAAGACUGGCUCUCCAGGAGGCCCUGGUGUGAGUGGUGGUAGCCCUGCAGGUGGGGCUGGAGGUGGAAGCAGUGGUUUACCACCAUCCACCAAAAAGUCAGGCCAGAAGCCUGUCUUAGAUGUUCAUGCAGAACUAGACAGAAUUACACGAAAACCAGUUACAGUUUCUCCCACAACACCUACAUCUCCUACGGAAGGAGAAGCUUCUUGAAGAUACCAAAUAAAGCCAUUUAUUCUGUUUUCUGGGAUAAUGUAAACAUGCCUCUGCCUUUUCCUUCAAAAGUGGAAUUAGAAAGCUGGAGUGCUUCUUCAGAUGGACUAAAUUUAUGUCGUGUGUGUGUGUGUGUGUGUGUGUGGUUACCCAUUUUUUAGAAGGAGCCGUACAGAAGAAAAAUUAUUCUACAUUAUGUAGGAUUGCUGUUUGCAUUGCCAUUUUGCAUAAGAAAGUAAUUUUUGAUUUUGAAAAUCUCAAAACUUUUAGAUCUGAAAUACAGCCAUGUGAUCGAUCAUAUUCUAAAGGCUAUUUAAAACAUGUAAAAGGAUUUGGGGAACGGCAGAAAACAUGCAGUUUGGGCAUUUGACUGACUUGGAAGUCUAAGCUUAUUUUAGUUAUAACUAUUAAAAUCAUUUUUAAAAAUUUGUUAGUUUUGCUGACAGAGAAAAAUCGUCAGUUGUCAGAUUUUGCACACCACAAUAAAUGUACCACCACACACGGAAUAUGCUAAGAAAACUAUCAGAUAGCGUUUGAUACACUAGUCAUUGUCUCAAUCACUGAUCCUGUAAGUUGUCAUCAAAAUAUGAUUUAGAAAUAUUGGCCAAGGUGUUGCUUUAACUGAGGAGAAAAGAAAGCACACUGCCUAAAUGUGUAAAAGAAAAAUGCAGAGGUUAUUAAAAUGUAAAGAAGUAACAAUCUUUGGAUUUGUCUAUACAUAUAUAUAUAUAUAUAUGGCUUUGCCUUAAUAUACCCCCUUUUUUGUUUGUGACUUUCAACUGUAAUCAGUUAAUAAAGUAUUUAUUCUCUGCAUUCAGGUUCAAA